CUCCGCGGACGCCCGCUGCCAUGGCGACUCUGCUGCGCCCUGUCCUCCGUCGGCUCUGCGGGCUCCCGGGCCUACAGCGGCCUGCGGCAGAAAUGCCCCUCCGGGCUAGGAGCGACGGCGCCGGCCCGCUAUACUCGCACCACCUCCCCACCUCCCCGCUGCAGAAAGGGCUGUUGGCCGCCGGCUCCGCGGCGAUGGCGCUCUAUAACCCCUACCGCCACGACAUGGUCGCAGUUCUAGGGGAGACCACAGGACACCGCACCCUGAAGGUCCUCAGGGACCAGAUGAGGAGGGAUCCAGAGGGUGCCCAGAUCCUGCAGGAGCGUCCCCGGAUUUCGACAUCCACCCUCGACCUGGGCAAGCUCCAGAGCCUGCCGGAAGGCUCCCUCGGUCGCGAGUAUCUCCGUUUCCUGGAUGUGAACGGACAUUGCUUUCCCUACGGUAUGGCAGGUGUGGCACUCUCCAGCCCCUCCAGCCCCAGGCAGGGAGGACAAGGAGAGGGGGAAAGGGGGUGUCCCGACUAUUGGCAAACUCAUUCACUAACUGAGGCUCUGCUAUGUGCCAUCCCUUUUUUUUUUUGAGUCGCUCUGUCGCCCAGGCUAGAGUGCAGUGGUGCGAUCUCUGCUCACUGCAAGCUCCGCCUCCCAGGUACACGCCAUUCUCCUGCCUCAGCCUCCCGAGUAGCUGGGACUACAGGCGCCCGCCACGACGCCCGGCUAAUUUUUUGUAUUUUUUAGUAGAGACGGGGUUUCACCGUGCUAGCCAGGAUGGUCUCGAUCUCCUGACCACGUGAUCCGCCCGCAUCAGCCUCCCAAAGUGCUGGGAUUACAGGCGUGAGCCACAGCGCCCGGCCCAUCCUUUUUGUUUUGUUUUGUUUUGAGACAGGGUCCCGCUCUGCCACCCAGGCUGGAGUGCAGUGGCGCCGUCUCGGCUCACUGCAACUCAGCUUCCUGGGUUCAAGCGAUUCUCCUGCCUCAACCCCCCACGUAGCUGGGACUACAGGUGCACACCACAACGCCCAGCUAAUUUUUGUACUUUUAGUAGAGAGGGGUUUUACCAUAUUAACCAGGCUGGUCUUGAACUCCUGACCUCAAGUGAUCCACCUGCCUCAGCCUCCCAAAAUGCUGGGACUACAGGUGUGAGCCACCGUGCCCAGCCCAACCAUUGUUUUGUGUACAGGGGAUAUAAUGGUGAACUAGACAGCCAAGUUCCCUGCCCUCAUUUCUAUUCUACUUCGAGAGGUAGACAAUAAAAUAGUUUUUAAAAAUUUUCAGGGAAGGCACAGUGGCUCACAUCUGUAAUCCCAGCACUUUGGGAGGCUGGCGGGAGGACCACCUAAGGUCAGGAGUUUGAGACCAGUCUGACCAACAUGGUGGAAACCUGUCUCUACUAAAAAUACAAAAAUUAGCUAGGUGUGAUGGUGUGCGCCUGUAAUCCCAGCUACUCGGGAGGCUGAGGCAGGAGAAUUGAUUGAACCCGGGAGGCACAGGUUGCAGUGAGCUGAGAUCACACCACUGCACUCCAGCCUGGGCGACAGAGUGAGACUCUGUCUCCAACAAAACAAAACAAAAAAAUUCAUAUAAAAAUACAGGUAAAAUGUUUCAAGUAAUUAGAAUAUUCUGGCACUGGUCCAUGCGUGUUGGCUCAUGCCUGUAAUCCUAAUACUUUGGGGGGCUGAAGUGGGCGGAUCACUUGAGCCCAGGAGUUUGAGACCAGCCUGGACAACAUGGUGAAACCCUGUCUCUGCAAAAAAUGCAAAAAUUAGCCAAGUGUGGUGGUGUAUACCCAUAGUCCCAGCUACCUGGGAGGGAGUUUGAGGUAGGAGGAUCAGUUGAGCCCAGGAGGUCGAGGGCGGUGAGCCGUAAUCACACCACUACACUCCAGCUUGGACAACAGAGCAAGACUCUGUCUCAAAAAUAAAAAAAAGUAUACCAGCA